GUAAAUCCUAGAGAGGCGGGCUAAGCUGGACUGGGGGGAGGGUCCGUCUUCCGGAAAGUCUGGAUUCCCGGACGAGCCGAGUUGCUGCUCACCGAACUCCCGUUCGAGAGAUGAUCGAAGAAAGUCGGCUACCAUUUGUACCCAUCAAAGAUCUCCAGAUGGAAGCCAGCGCUGAAUUUGGGCUGAGAUUAGGACUUGCAGGAGGCCGGUCCAGAAGACGGCGGAAGGAAUCUUGGCGGGCGCACGCAUGCGUGAUAGACCCUCCACACGUGUGGCCGGGCCGCGGCCUCCCCGUGCUCGGAGGUCCCGCCCCCGGCCGUAGCAUCUUUCCGGACGUGGGGAGCCGGUUGUAAAGAAGAAAGUUCUACCCUUUCUGUCAAAAUGAAGUGUGAUUUUAAUUGUAACCAUGUUCAUUCCGGACUUAAACUGGUAAAACCUGAUGACAUUGGAAGACUAGUUUCCUACACCCCUGCAUAUUUGGAAGGUUCCUGUAAAGACUGCAUUAAAGACUAUGAAAGGCUGUCAUGUAUUGGGUCACCGAUUGUGAGCCCUAGGAUUGUACAACUUGAAACUGAAAGCAAGCGCUUGCAUAACAAGGAAAAUCAACAUGUGCAACAGACACUUAAUAGUACAAAUGAAAUAGAAGCACUAGAGACCAGUAGACUUUAUGAAGACAGUGGCUAUUCCUCAUUUUCUCUACAAAGUGGCCUCAGUGAACAUGAAGAAGGUAGCCUCCUGGAGGAGAAUUUCGGUGACAGUCUACAAUCCUGCCUGCUACAAAUACAAAGCCCAGACCAAUAUCCCAACAAAAACUUGCUGCCAGUUCUUCAUUUUGAAAAAGUGGUUUGUUCAACAUUAAAAAAGAAUGCAAAACGAAAUCCUAAAGUAGAUCGGGAGAUGCUGAAGGAAAUUAUAGCCAGAGGAAAUUUUAGACUGCAGAAUAUAAUUGGCAGAAAAAUGGGCCUAGAAUGUGUAGAUAUUCUCAGCGAACUCUUUCGAAGGGGACUCAGACAUGUCUUAGCAACUAUUUUAGCACAACUCAGUGACAUGGACUUAAUCAAUGUGUCUAAAGUGAGCACAACUUGGAAGAAGAUCCUAGAAGAUGAUAAGGGGGCAUUCCAGUUGUACAGUAAAGCAAUACAAAGAGUUACCGAAAACAACAAUAAAUUUUCACCUCAUGCUUCAACCAGAGAAUAUGUUAUGUUCAGAACCCCACUGGCUUCUGUUCAGAAAUCAGCAGCCCAGACUUCUCUCAAAAAAGAUGCUCAAACCAAGUUAUCCAAUCAAGGUGAUCAGAAAGGUUCUACUUAUAGUCGACACAAUGAAUUCUCUGAGGUUGCCAAGACAUUGAAAAAGAACGAAAGCCUCAAAGCCUGUAUUCGCUGUAAUUCACCUGCAAAAUAUGAUUGCUAUUUACAACGGGCAACCUGCAAACGAGAAGGCUGUGGAUUUGAUUAUUGUACGAAGUGUCUCUGUAAUUAUCAUACUACUAAAGACUGUUCAGAUGGCAAGCUCCUCAAAGCCAGUUGUAAAAUAGGUCCCCUGCCUGGUACAAAGAAAAGCAAAAAGAAUUUACGAAGAUUGUGAUCUCUUAUUAAAUCAAUUGUUACUGAUCAUGAAUGUUAGUUAGAAAAUGUUAGGUUUUAACUUAAAAAAAAUUGUAUUGUGAUUUUCAAUUUUAUGUUGAAAUCGGUGUAGUAUCCUGAGGUUUUUUUCCCCCCAGAAGAUAAAGAGGAUAGACAACCUCUUAAAAUAUUUUUACAAUUUAAUGAGAAAAAGUUUAAAAUUCUCAAUACAAAUCAAACAAUUUAAAUAUUUUAAGAAAAAAGGAAAAGUAGAUAGUGAUACUGAGGGUAAAAAAAAAUUGAUUCAAUUUUAUGGUAAAGGAAACCCAUGCAAUUUUACCUAGACAGUCUUAAAUAUGUCUGGUUUUCCAUCUGUUAGCAUUUCAGACAUUUUAUGUUCCUCUUACUCAAUUGAUACCAACAGAAAUAUCAACUUCUGGAGUCUAUUAAAUGUGUUGUCACCUUUCUAAAGCUUUUUUUCAUUGUGUGUAUUUCCCAAGAAAGUAUCCUUUGUAAAAACUUGCUUGUUUUCCUUAUUUCUGAAAUCUGUUUUAAUAUUUUUGUAUACAUGUAAAUAUUUCUGUAUUUUUUAUAUGUCAAAGAAUAUGUCUCUUGUAUGUACAUAUAAAAAUAAAUUUUGCUCAAUAAAA